AUUUCACUUUCAUUCUUAAAGUAUAUUUUUGCUGGAUAUAGAAUCCUCAGUUGGCAGCUCAUUUCUCUCACAACUUUAAAGAUGUUAUUUCACUUCCUUCUGGCCCACAUGGUUUAUAAUGAAAAAUUCAGUUUUCUGAAUCCCAUUGUUCUUUAGUCGUGUGUUGUUUAAGAUUUUUUUCUUUGUUUCAGUGUUUAGAAUUUUUGAUUAUAAUGUGUCAAGAGUAUAGACUUCUUUGAGUUUAUUCUAUUUGGCAUUCCUUAAGCUUCUUUAAUCUUUAGGCUUAUGUCUUUUCACACAUUUGGGAAUUUUUCAGAAAUUAUUUCUUCAAAAUUUUUGUGUGUACUGCACUUUAUCCUCUUAAUCUGGAAUUCCAAUGACAUUAAUUUUGGACUUUUGAUAUUGCCCUACAGGUCCCUGAAGUUCUGUUAACUUUUUUUUUCCCAAUGUUUUUUCUCUCUCUUGUUCUGAUUGGAUUAUUUCUGUUGACCCAUCUUCAAGUUGACUGACUCUUCUGUCAUUUCUAUCCCGCUUGGAGCUCAUCCAAUGGUCAGGACCAAGUAGGAGUGGGGCAGCUUUGGCCCCUCCAAGGAUUUGCCACCCCAGUCUUCCAGCAUUUACAGGUUGUGCUCCAGCAGAUUAUACCCCAAGGUCUGUUCUGGAAGGAUGACAUCACCCAGGAUGCAAUGAUCCAAAAGAUGGAGCAUGCCAGCAGACUGCAUCCCCAAGAACCAUGCCUGAAGGAUGGGAAGGCACUUUUCCCCACUAAAACCACUGAGAGCCCCCUGGCCAAGGUGAACAGGGAUCAGUGCUUUACCUCCGAAGUGGUUUCUAAGGCCCUGAAACAAGAGGUGGCCAACCCUGUCAAGAUUACCUAUAGGUGUUCAUAUGGGGGGCUGGACAUGAUGCAGGCGCCGGGACCCUCUAAGGAAGAAAUUAUCUAUAAGAUCAUGCGGCUUCUCUGGGCCACUUCCUACUGUGGGCCGCAACCCUGUGGCUGAUUGAGACCUCAUGUGAAGCCUCCCUGCCCCAGCACCCUUCCCAUUGCCCUUCAGAGGAGCAGUUCUUGGAUGACCCAGAUUUGAAUCAUUAAAGUAGACUCUCAUGCAAA